AGACGGAGCAGAGCGGUCAGGGAUCAUGAGGGAGAGUGCGUUGGAGCGGGGGCCUGUGCCCGAGGCGCCGGCGGGGGGUCCCGUGCACGCCGUGACGGUGGUGACCCUGCUGGAGAAGCUGGCCUCCAUGCUGGAGACUCUGCGGGAGCGGCAGGGAGGCCUGGCUCGAAGGCAGGGAGGCCUGGCAGGGUCCGUGCGCCGCAUCCAGAGCGGCCUGGGCGCUCUGAGUCGCAGCCACGACACCACCAGCAACACCUUGGCGCAGCUGCUGGCCAAGGCGGAGCGCGUGAGCUCGCACGCCAACGCCGCCCAAGAGCGCGCGGUGCGCCGCGCAGCCCAGGUGCAGCGGCUGGAGGCCAACCACGGGCUGCUGGUGGCGCGCGGGAAGCUCCACGUUCUGCUCUUCAAGGAGGAGGGUGAAGUCCCAGCCAGCGCUUUCCAGAAGGCACCAGAGCCCUUGGGCCCGGCGGACCAGUCCGAGCUGGGCCCAGAGCAGCUGGAGGCCGAAGUUGGAGAGAGCUCGGACGAGGAGCCGGUGGAGUCCAGGGCCCAGCGGCUGCGGCGCACCGGAUUGCAGAAGGUACAGAGCCUCCGAAGGGCCCUUUCGGGCCGGAAAGGCCCUGCAGCGCCACCGCCCACCCCGGUCAAGCCGCCUCGCCUUGGGCCUGGCCGGAGCGCUGAAGCCCAGCCGGAAGCCCAGCCUGCGCUGGAGCCCACGCUGGAGCCAGAGCCUCCGCAGGACACCGAGGAAGAUCCCGGGAGACCUGGGGCUGCCGAAGAAGCUCUGCUCCAAAUGGAGAGUGUAGCCUGAGGGCUGGUGUUGCCUGCCUCCCCUGUGCUUGUGCCUUGUCCCAAAAUAAAUCCUUUCAGAAUGUAGCACUCACGCCCUAAUAAGGAGCGAAUCCUACAUCCACCAAGGCGGGCGCUCUGGCCCUCCCUUCCUUAAGCCCAGUCCUGUGUCCUCUGAAAGAGGUGCAGUCACUCACACCUGCUUGCGCUCACCAUCAAUAAAAGUAAUUUCACCCGAA